CCCAGGCAGACUGAGGAGUCCCUGUGUUUUUGGCAAAGGUAGCUCUACUAGAAAUAUGGAGAGCGGAAACCAAUCAACAGUGACUGAAUUUAUCUUCACUGGAUUCCCUCAGCUUCAGGAUGGUAGUCUCCUGUACUUCUUUCCUUUACUUUUCAUCUAUACUUUUAUUAUCAUUGAUAACUUAUUAAUCUUCUCUGCUGUAAGGCUGGACACCCAUCUCCACAACCCCAUGUAUAAUUUUAUCAGUAUAUUUUCCUUUCUGGAGAUCUGGUACACCACAGCCACCAUUCCCAAGAUGCUCUCCAACCUCAUCAGUGAAAAGAAGGCCAUCUCAAUGACUGGCUGCAUCUUGCAGAUGUAUUUCUUCCACUCACUUGAAAACUCAGAGGGGAUCUUGCUGACCACCAUGGCCAUUGACAGAUACGUUGCCAUCUGCAACCCUCUUCGCUAUCAAAUGAUCAUGACCCCCCGGCUCUGUGCUCAACUCUCUGCAGGUUCCUGCCUCUUCGGUUUCCUUAUCCUGCUUCCCGAGAUUGUGAUGAUUUCCACACUGCCUUUCUGUGGGCCCAACCAAAUCCAUCAGAUCUUCUGUGACUUGGUCCCUGUGCUAAGCCUGGCCUGUACAGACACGUCCAUGAUUCUGAUUGAGGAUGUGAUUCAUGCUGUGACCAUCAUCAUUACCUUCCUAAUCAUUGCCCUGUCCUAUGUAAGAAUUGUCACUGUGAUAUUGAGGAUUCCCUCUUCUGAAGGGAGGCAAAAGGCUUUUUCUACCUGUGCAGGCCACCUCAUGGUCUUCCCGAUAUUCUUUGGCAGUGUAUCACUCAUGUACUUGCGUUUCAGCGACACUUAUCCACCAGUUUUGGACACAGCCAUUGCACUGAUGUUUACUGUACUUGCUCCAUUCUUCAAUCCCAUCAUUUAUAGCCUGAGAAACAAGGACAUGAACAAUGCGAUUAAAAAACUGUUCUGUCUUCAAAAAGUGUUGAACAAGCCUGGAGGUUAAUACAGAGCCACAGGUUCCCUUCCGUUGCUUUUGUUUUGUUUUGUUUUUUGAGAUGGAGUUUCACUCUUGUUGCCUGGGCUGGAGUGCAAUGGCAUGAUCUUGGCUCACUGCAACCUCCACCUCCUGGUUUUGAACAAUUCUCCUGCCUCAGCCUCCCUAGUAGCCGCGAUUACAGGCAUGCACCACCACACCCAGCUAAUUUUUGUAUUUUUAGUGGAGAUGGGGUUUCACUGUGUUGGUCAGGCUGGUCUUGAACUCCUGACCUUAGGUGAUCCAAACUCCUCUGCCUCCCAAAAUGCUGGGAUUACAGCUGUGAGCCACCGCAUCUGGCCCUUUCCAUUGCUUUAAUGUUUGUCUAACAUAUUAGAACAUGAGAUUACUCUAUACCUAGUGCUUUGUCACACUGAAAUUUCUGUCAUCCUAAUUAUUUUCCCUAUACCUAGAAAAAUAUUUAUACUCUCUGUGUCAUCGUUAUAAAAGUUGCUGUGCAUAUCAUGAGGAACCUUAUUAUGUGGCUGAAUAACUGUAGUUUCUUUCUUCUGAAAUGCUGUGGUUAAAGAAAAUUUGUUUGCCACUUUAGAGGGUUAGAACUACAGAGCUUGAGCUUCAGAAGCUGACAAUGUGCUCUGUGGUAGUAUGUGUCUAUUUAGGUAACACAUCUUAGAAAAGUUUUUUUGUUUAAUUAUGAGUCAUGGAUUACCUCAUUGGGGUUUUCCAGAAAUAGAGAUCUAAGAAAAAGCCCAAACAACAUUUAAUUAAGUUAUAUCUUUAUUUUUAGUUAUGUAGUUACCUAUUCAUUAGAAUAAUUACAUGUUUAGUAAGAUUAGAUUAUUAGUACUGC